AUUAAUUAAUUUAUUUUUUGCCACCCAGGCUUAUCUCAAACUUCUGGCCCCCAUCAAUCCUCCCACCUCAGCCUUCCAAAGUGUUGGGAUUACAGUCAUAAGCCACUGCAUCUGGCUUGGAUCUUUUGCUGACCUCAAAAUGUUGGACAUCCUCAAAGUUGAUACCUAGACUUCAUCCAUACUCACUUCCCCAAAUUAUAUAAUUAUGUCACUUCAUGUGCCACUUUAAGCUUAAAUGCAAGCUUAUUUCUCCAGCUUUCACCUCUCUUUUAAAUACCUCUUAUGUACUUAACUGCAUUCGGGUAUCUAAUAGACAUCUUAAUAAACAUCUUAAACUUAACAUCAGGUGUUUAACAGGCAUCUUAAACUCAAACAGAUCUCUUGAUCUUCCACCUGUACUACCACCACCACAAAACUUAACCUAUUUUCCCCCACAACUUCUCCAAUUCAGGAAAUGUCACUACCAUUCUUCCAGUUGCUGUGGCCAAAAAUCUAAGAGUCAUACUUAAUUCCCCUCUCUCUCCUUUUGCACUUUCUAUUUAAUCCAUAAGCAAUUCCUAUUAAUUCUACUUUCAGAAUUUAUACUAAAGUCUGACCACUUCAUAUCACCAGCACUGUCUAAUCUUAGCCACUAUCUUUACUCUCCUACACUAAAUUCCCACUAACGUUCUCCCUGCUUUUCUUUCACUUCUAUACUGCUUUCCUCACAGUGUCUGAGUGAUAUUGUAAAUUAAGUAAGAAUUGUCCAUAGCUCCCCAUCACACCUAGAAUGAAAUCCAAAACUAUUGCCAAGUCCAUAAAGUGCCCAUGACUGGAUCCUUCCUAUUUCUCAGACACCGAUAACUAACCCCUGCCCCCUUACUUGGUCAGCUCCAGGUGCCCUUGCCUUCUCAUUCCUCCUUGUACAAGCGUAUUUCCUCCUCAGGAUACUUGCAUUCGAUGUUUUCUCUGCCAGGGAUGCUCUUUCCCAAAUAUUCAGAAGGCUUGUUUCCUGAUUUCAUUUAGGUUUUUACUGAAUCUAUCUAAAUCUAUCUAAACAGUUAAGACCAUCUUAAGAUGCUCUGUAUCUUAUUUCUCUGCUUUAUUUUUCUUAGAGAACCAAUCACCCUCUGAAAGAAUAUUAUAUACUUAUUUUUAAAUUGGCUCUCUACCACUAUAAUAUGAAUUUCUUGACAUCAAAGAUUGUCAUUCAUGUUUACUCCCAUCACUCCAGGGCCAUGCACAACGUCUGGCAUACAGUGAGCACUUCAAAUUAUUUGCUGUAUGGACAAGUGUAUGGAAUAUGAUUUUAUGCUCUCUCCUAUUGACACUUUUCUCCUACCUAAGGAACUAAUUAUUCAAGUAAACAUUUAACCUAAGAAAAAGUAAGUAUCUCAAACCAAGCUUGGCUAAAAUAAAUAAUAGUAAUGACACAAUAUUUACUGAAUAAGUAAAUUCCAGGCACUAGUCUAAGCUCCUUAAUCUUCACAAAAACUCUGUGAGGUAGGUACCACAAUUAUCUACACUUUACCGACAAGGAAACUAAAGCACAGAGAGGUGAAACAUUUCUCCCACAGUCACACAGCUUGUAAGAGGAAGAGCCAGUACUCAAAUCUGUGUCAUCCAGCUACAAAGCCUCCAUUUUCCCCAGAAUUAUUUUUUCUUGAUCAUUGAGCCAUAAUAUUAUGGUCAAGUCCUUGGGAUAGAAGAGAAUUUUUGGAGAAAUUUGAAUUCCUUUUCUGGACCUAAGCCUCCUCUGAUCUGAAAUUGGUAAACAAAGGGUCUCUAUGCCUUGAGUAUGAGGCUGUGCACUCUCCUUGCCUGACUCUGUUGUUCCCUUGAGAGAGUCAAUCCAAAGCUGGAUCCUCAAGACUUUUGAAAGGAGGCGGUGGGAAUGGGAAUGAGGAGCUUGAAGAAGGAGCUGCUAAGUAGUUAGCAAAGAUGCCACCUCCUAGUCACAGACAACACAAGUCAUUGGCAAUUACUUUGUGAUCAUAAAAAAGAACGAUGUGUUGUUCUGUGGGCAGGUGCUCUGUGGGUGAUGCAGAAUAUGGGAAAAGGAGCAGAGAGAAAGAAGAAAAGAAGCAGGGGUAAGAUAAGGAGGGAGGAAGAGAAGAUGAAAGAAGGAAGGGGAGAAGAGAGAAAGAGGGAAAGAGGGAGGAAGAGAGAGAUGCAGGGAGGGUCCAGGGGAUGGAGGGUGUGGUGUUGGGGAAGCUCUCAAAGGAUUUAAACUUUGGAGAUUUGUGGGAUUUGCUGCUCUGUACUGAUCUCUGCUGAAUUCUCUCCCAGCUCCACUCUGUGAACCUGCCGGGGUCCCUGUCGCUGAUGUGAGCUUGGAGACUCAGCCCCCAGGAGGACAGUCCCGGUGUCUCGCCCAAUCCUCAUGCUCAGGGCUCCCAGGGCCCAGGCUGCAGUGGAGGAUGUGCUGGAGCUUCACUGUGAGGCCCUGAGAGGCUCUCCUCCGAUCCUGUACUGGUUUUAUCACGAGGAUAUCACCCUGGGGAGCAGGUCGGCCCCCUCUGGAGGAGGAGCCUCCUUCAACCUUUCCCUGACUGAAGAACAUUCUGGAAACUACUCCUGUGAGGCCAACAAUGGCCUGGGGGCCCAGCGCAGUGAGGCGGUGACACUCAACUUCACAGUGCCUACUGGGGCCAGAAGCAAUCAUCUUACCUCAGGAGUCAUUGAGGGGCUGCUCAGCACCCUUGGUCCAGCCACCGUGGCCUUAUUAUUUUGCUACGGCCUCAAAAGAAAAAUAGGAAGACGUUCAGCCAGGGAUCCACUCAGGAGCCUUCCCAGCCCUCUACCCCAAGAGUUCACCUACCUCAACUCACCUACCCCAGGGCAGCUACAGCCUAUAUAUGAAAAUGUGAAUGUUGUAAGUGGGGAUGAGGUUUAUUCACUGGCGUACUAUAACCAGCCGGAGCAGGAAUCAGUAGCAGCAGAAACCCUGGGGACACAUAUGGAGGACAAGGUUUCCUUAGACAUCUAUUCCAGGCUGAGGAAAGCAAACAUUACAGAUGUGGACUAUGAAGAUGCUAUGUAAGGUUAUGGAAGAUUCUGCUCUUUGAAAACCAUCCAUGACCCCAAGCCUCAGGCCUGAUAUGUUCUUCAGAGAUCCUGGGGCAUUAGCUUUCCAGUAUACCUCUUCUGGAUGCCAUUCUCCAUGGCACUAUUCCUUCAUCUACUGUGAAGUGAAGUUGGCGCAGCCCUGAAGAAACUACCUAGGAGAACUAAUAGACACAGGAGUGACAGGGACUUUGUUAUCAGAACCAGAUUCCUGCCGGCUCCUUUGAAAACAGGUCAUAUUGUGCUCUUCUGUUUACAAGAGGAAACAAGAUGGAAUAAAAGAAAUUGGGAUCUUGGGUUGGAGGGACAGUGAAGCUUAGAGCACAUGAACUCAAGGUUAGUGACUCUGCAGGACUUCACAGAGAGAGCUGUGCCCAUCAUUCAGUCCAAGUGCUUUCUCUGCCCAGACAGCACAGAACUCCAGCCCCGCUACUUACAUGGAUCAUCGAGUUUCCACCUAAAAUAUGAUUCUAUUUAUUUUGAGUCACUGUUACCAAAUUAGAACUAAAACAAAGUUACAUAAAAAGUUAUUGUGACUCCACUUAAUUUUAGUGACGUAUUUUUGUAUAUAUAGGCCAACCUAUACCACAUCCAAAAUUAUGUAUCUAUUACAGCCCCUAGAAGCUUUAUAAAUACAGUGUGUCUUCUUUUAUUCACAAAAUUUUUGAAAUCGUGGUAAUAUGGUUUGAAACCUGUAUCUUAAUUAUUUUUUUUUUAAAUUGAGACAGGGUCUCACUCUGUCACUCAAUCUGGAAUGCAGUGGCACAAUCUUGCCUCACUGCAACGCCUGCCUCUCAGGCUCAAGCAAACCUCUCACCUCAGCCUGCUGAGUAGCUGGGACUACAGGCACAUGCCACCAAACUUGGCCAUUUUUUGUCUUACGUAGAGACAAGAUUUCACCGUUUUGCCCAGGCUGGUCUCAAACUCCUGGGCUCAAGCAAUGUAUUGAAUUUUAAAAUAACCAGGCACUCACUCUUAUGAAUUAAUAAACAUUUGGAGGUAUAUAAAGUAAAAAGUUAAAGUCUUUCCUGUAAGUUAACACAAAUGUUAACUAUUGUUAAAAACUUUACAGGUAGCUCUCUAGAUAUUUUUCUAUUUUUGUAUGUAUACUUAUGCAUACAUGUAAGUAUAUAAACAUUUAGAAGUGUACCUAUCUAACAAACUAUUAUGAAAUACUUUCAAAUCUGUAAAUAGAUCUAUUAUACUAUUUUAAAAGUCUCUAUAGUAGUGUGUUAUAUAGAUAAAUCAUAACUUUUUUCUUUUUUUAUUGUAGUAAAUAUGCACAACAUAAAAUUGAUCAUUUUAACCAUUUUUAAGUGUACAAUUCAGUGGCAUUAAGUACUAUCAUAAUAUAUUUUAAUCCUUCUCAUCACUGGUGGACAUUAAGGAGACUCUCAAAAAAUUCAUAUUAUAAAAACAAAGUUCAAACAAAUGUCUUUGUACUAGCAUAUUAUGGCACUCCUGCUGGAUUAUCUGAAGGAUAAAUUUGUAAAUCUAGUAUUGCUAGAUUAUGCAUAUUAAAUAUUCUUGUUAAAUAGUCUUCAAUGUCUCUCAGGUAAGGCUGUAUCAAUUUAUAUCUUCACCAACAACGUCUGGGAAAUCAGUUUGUGGGGUGUAUUACUUAGUUUUCACAUUGCUAAUAAAGACAUAUCCAAGACUGGGUAAUUUAUAAA